AGUGCCUGCAGCCGGUGCUGUCCACAGGGAGCUCCAGCCCUUCUCACACUCGACCCGCAGAGGAUGGCCCUAGAGGAGUCUGUGGCGUUUGGGGCCUGAACCAGCUGGGAGGACAGCACGAGGGGCUGGUGGGCAGCCUGGGACUGGGUCACACCGGGGGCCUGGACAACACUGGCUCGUGGGGCUGAGGACUGAGGAGAGCCUGGCCCAGCCGUGGCAGUUACAAGAGGCUUAACCUGAGGGGCAGCAGAGUCUCAGGAAGAGAUUCUGGGAUAGGAAAAAGCUACCCCCGUUGCCUGGAAGACAGCUAUCUGCUGGAAACCACCCACCUUCACCAUGUCUGACGAGGAAGUUGAACAGGUGGAGGAGCAGUACGAAGAAGAAGAGGAAGCCCAGGAGGAAGAGGAAGUUCAAGAAGAGGAGAAACCGAGACCCAAACUCACUGCUCCUAAGAUCCCAGAAGGGGAGAAAGUGGACUUCGAUGACAUCCAGAAGAAGCGUCAGAACAAAGACCUAAUGGAGCUCCAGGCCCUCAUCGACAGCCACUUUGAAGCCCGGAAGAAGGAGGAGGAGGAGCUGGUCGCUCUCAAAGAGAGAAUCGAGAAGCGCCGUGCAGAGAGAGCGGAGCAGCAGAGGAUUCGUGCAGAGAAGGAGAGGGAGCGCCAGAACAGACUGGCGGAGGAAAAGGCCAGAAGGGAGGAGGAGGAUGCCAAGAGGAGGGCAGAGGACGACCUGAAGAAGAAGAAAGCUCUGUCUUCCAUGGGAGCCAACUACAGCAGCUACCUGGCCAAGGCUGACCAGAAGAGAGGCAAGAAGCAGACAGCCCGGGAAAUGAAGAAGAAGAUUCUGGCUGAGAGACGCAAGCCGCUCAACAUCGAUCACCUUGGUGAAGACAAACUGAGGGACAAGGCCAAGGAGCUCUGGGAGACCCUGCACCAGCUGGAGAUUGACAAGUUCGAGUUUGGGGAGAAGCUGAAACGCCAGAAAUAUGACAUCACCACGCUCAGGAGCCGCAUUGACCAGGCCCAGAAGCACAGCAAGAAGGCUGGGACCCCAGCCAAGGGCAAAGUCGGCGGGCGCUGGAAGUAGAGAGGCCAGAAAGGCCCCUCGAGGCAGAGACCCUCCGCCCUCUUGCACACCAGGGCCGCUCGUGGGACUCCACAUCCUCCAGCCCCCACAAUCCUGUCAGGGGCUCCCUGACAGUCCUGGGGGUGGAGAGGCCAUCCCGGGGCGUCCCCCGCGUCUGUGUCCUUGCUGCCUUCAUCCCCUGGGGCCUGUGAAUAAAGCUGCAGAACCCCC